AGAUUUCGUUUCCUGCAUCUCCAAACAUGGCGACCUAGGAGAAGGGGAAGAACAAUUUUUUCUCCUCUUUUGGGAAGGUUUGUGUCUAGUAGUGCCUGUGCCCCUGGGCAGAUUGGAGAGAAGAGGGACGACUGGAGAAUCGUCGAGAACCAGCGGAGAAAAGAAAAAGCAACGUUUAAUUCUAGAAGGCCUCCUGUCCCUGCCUGCUCUGGGUGCUCAUGGAAUCAGCUGCUGCCCUGCACUUCUCCCGGCCAGCCUCCCUCCUCCUCCUCCUCCUCAGCCUGUGUGCACUGGUCUCAGCCCAGUUUAUUGUCGUGGGGCCCACUGAUCCCAUCUUGGCCACGGUUGGAGAAAACACUACGUUACGCUGCCAUCUGUCACCCGAGAAAAAUGCUGAGGACAUGGAGGUGCGGUGGUUCCGGUCUCAGUUCUCCCCCGCAGUGUUUGUGUAUAAAGGUGGCAGAGAGAGAACAGAGGAGCAGAUGGAGGAGUACCGAGGAAGAACCACCUUUGUGAGCAAAGACAUCAGCAGGGGCAGCGUGGCCCUGGUCAUACACAACAUCACAGCCCAGGAAAACGGCACCUACCGCUGUUACUUCCAAGAAGGCAGGUCCUACGAUGAGGCCAUCCUGCACCUCGUAGUGGCAGGACUAGGCUCUAAGCCCCUCAUUUCAAUGAGGGGCCAUGAAGACGGGGGCAUCCGGCUGGAGUGCAUAUCUAGAGGGUGGUACCCAAAGCCCCUCACAGUGUGGAGGGACCCCUACGGUGGGGUUGCGCCUGCCCUGAAAGAGGUCUCCAUGCCUGAUGCAGACGGCCUCUUCAUGGUCACCACGGCUGUGAUCAUCAGAGACAAGUCUGUGAGGAACAUGUCCUGCUCUAUCAACAACACCCUGCUCGGCCAGAAGAAAGAAAGUGUCAUUUUUAUUCCAGAAUCCUUUAUGCCCAGUGUGUCUCCCUGUGCAGUGGCCCUGCCUAUCAUUGUGGUUAUUCUGAUGAUACCCAUUGCCGUAUGCAUCUAUUGGAUCAACAAACUCCAAAAGGAAAAAAAGAUUCUGUCAGGGGAAAAGGAGUUUGAACGGGAAACAAGAGAAAUUGCUCUAAAGGAACUGGAGAAAGAACGUGUGCAAAAAGAGGAAGAACUUCAAGUAAAAGAGAAACUUCAAGAAGAAUUGCGAUGGAGAAGAACAUUCUUACAUGCUGAGCUCCAAUUCUUCUCAAACUGAGAGAACUGCUUCUGUCUCUGGAGAGACAGAAGUGCAGCUUCAGUAAUUCUCAGUGUGUGAGCUGCCUAGGAUCAGAGAGCCUUCAUGGAAGUGGCCACUACGUGGGGAUCCCUUCAGAGAUAUCUGAGACCUCUCUGGGGAUCAGGAACCACACAAUCCCCAGGGUUCCUGAGACCCCAGGCCUAAACCUGAGACUUCCUCUGCAGUUGAUGUGGUCCUGGAUCCAGACACCGCUCAUCCCGAUCUCUUCCUGUCAGAGGACCGGAGAAGUGUGAGAAGGUGCCCCUUCAGGCACCUAGGGGAGAGCGUGCCUGACAACCCAGAGAGAUUCGACAGUCAGCCUUGUGUCCUAGGCCGGGAGAGCUUCGCUUCAGGGAAACAUUACUGGGAGGUGGAGGUGGAAAACGUGAUUGAGUGGACUGUGGGGGUCUGUAGAGACAGUGUUGAGAGGAAAGGGGAGGUCCUGCUGAUUCCUCAGAAUGGCUUCUGGACCUUGGAGAUGCAUAAAGGGCAAUACCGGGCCGUGUCCUCCCCUGAUAGGAUUCUCCCUUUGAAGGAGUCCCUUUGCCGGGUGGGCGUCUUCCUGGACUAUGAAGCUGGAGAUGUCUCCUUCUACAACAUGAGGGACAGAUCGCACAUCUACACAUGUCCCCGUUCAGCCUUUUCCGUGCCUGUGAGGCCCUUCUUCAGGUUGGGGUGUGAGGACAGCCCCAUCUUCAUCUGCCCUGCACUCACAGGAGCCAAUGGGGUCACGGUGCCUGAAGAGGGCCUGACACUUCACAGAGUGGGGACCCACCAGAGCCUAUAGAAUCAAUUCCUUGGUCUCACAGCCAUGUAGACAAGCCCUGGUCAUCUCAGCAGCCACCGCACAACACCCCUGGUGGAAGACACGCCCUCCUCCCCUCUGGUCACACAAGAGAACAUCUUCCAGCUGCCUCUUUCACACCCACUACAGACCUCAGCCCCAGUUUUCUCCUCCUCACUAGGCUGUGUUUUUAGUAGUUCCUUUGCUUGUAACUAUGGGAUGGGAUCCAGGCAUAGGGAACUAGUUGUUACACAGCUCCCAGCCAAGAAGAAAGUGUGAGAAGUUGAUGGGCAGCAAACCUGCUGUUUAACAUCAGGGUGACCACAUUAAGCCCAGUAUUCCAGUUGGCACCAGAAGAUAUGGACUUGGAAUGAGGCCUACAGGGUUCACCAGGAUGUAAGAGGAGAGAGGAAUCCACAGGACCACCAGAGAGGAGAGGGAACCAGAUAUGCAGAUCAGAGAUAGAGGAAGUGGAACCAGAGAGCUGGGAGGGACCAAGGUUGUAAGGGUGGCUAAGUCCCACCAUAACAGCUAAGGGGACCUGGGAGAUGAUGGCUCAUUUCCACCCAGCCCCAGGAUUUCCAGAGCGCACAUCCACAGGCCUGGACCUGGGAUGAAGAUGAAUGAAGAACAUGGAUGCACGUGGAUGUAGUUUGGCUCAGGUGUCCCUGCAGUUGGCAAGGAGUCAGUACUCAGUCCCUGAGUGUGGCUGAAAUUUGAGGUCCUGGCUGAGCCAAGGAGUAAUGGACCAGAUCUACCUCAGUAUUCAAGUUCAGUGGGGACACCAGUGGCUUCAAACUUCCUGGUUUCAUGAUAUCUUGAGACGCCUUACAAAUGAUGGAGGAUUCCAAAGAGUUUUUGUUUAUUUGGGUUAAUAUUUGUUGGUAUUUAUGGCAUUUGAGAUUGAAACUAAGAAAUGUUUUAAUUUAUUACCUUUACAACAUUUAUUUACAUUACAUACAUACAUUUACAACAUUUAUUAAUUUAUAUUAAAAUAGCAUGAAUAAGCCAAUUAUAGGUUAAUAUAAGUAGAAUGUUUGUGAAAAAUAAGUAUGGUAUCCAAAGCAAAAUAAAUUUUAUUGUGAAGUGUG